ACAGCUCGGAGCCACCAGGCGCUGACGAGGAGCCCGGCUGAGGGAGGAUGCGCCGCUGACGCCUGCGGGAGCCGCGCGCCUGGGGCGGGAGGAUGCUCCAGAGGGGCCUCUGGCCGUGGCGCACGCGGCUGCUGCCGACCCCUGGCACCUGGCGCCCAGCGCGCCCGUGGCCGCUGCCGCCUCCGCCCCAGGUAAGAGCGGGUGCCGGGCUGUGGGGGUUCGGGGUAGGCUGGUGCAAAGUUUGCGUUGGACAACUUUGGCGGGAGCAAAAGCCGAGCGGCCGAGCAGUCAACUGCGUUUUGCUGGCUGCCGGGCUCCGCGCGCCGGGCGGUCCCGACAGGUGGUGGCCGGGCGGCCGACGUGGGUCACGGAGGCCUGGGCUGAGGUCAAGACUCCGGGCCCGGGGAAGGUGAAGCCAGAGCGCUGCGGCUGGGGGUGCCUCACCCGGGCCGAGAUAGGGUGCGGGGACCACCAGACUUCGGCCUGGGAGCAGCAGAAUAACCUGGGAGGCAGUUUCUGGGCUGCAGCUCUCGGUCAGGAGCAAGUUUCCAAAGCCGCUGCGCCGCGGGGCCGGUUCCCUCUUGGUGAUCAGUGCCCGAGCCCCUAAGGAGCCCGGAAACGAUGAACGGGGCAGUGACCGUCCCGGGUGUGGACGGUCGCAGGAGAGUGAAAUUUCCAUCCUGAAAUCUGCGAGCACCUCCCUUUCCCAGAAGGAAGAAAAACUCGCGUUUUGUUCAGACACCCGAGAGACGGGUGAAUCAUGAGUGUGCUGGUUUUGCGUGUGAAGCUGUGUGGAAAUGUGAAAUACUACCAGUCACACCAUUAUAGUACCGUGGUGCCACCUGAUGAAAUAACAGUUAUUUAUAGACAUGGCCUUCCCUUGGUAACACUUACCUUGCCAUCUAGAAAAGAACGUUGUCAAUUCGUAGUCAAACCAAUGUUGUCAACAGUUGGUUCAUUCCUUCAGGACCUACAAAAUGAAGAUAAGGGUAUCAAAACUGCAGCCAUCUUCACAGCAGAUGGCAACAUGAUUUCAGCUUCUACCUUGAUGGAUAUUUUGCUAAUGAAUGAUUUUAAACUUGUCAUUAAUAAAAUAGCAUAUGAUGUGCAGUGUCCAAAGAGAGAAAAACCAAGUAAUGAGCACACUGCUGAGAUGGAACACAUGAAAUCUUUGGUUCACAGACUAUUUACAAUCUUGCAUUUAGAAGAGUCUCAGAAAAAGAGAGAGCACCAUUUACUGGAGAAAAUUGACCACCUGAAGGAACAGCUGCAGCCCCUUGAACAGGUGAAAGCUGGAAUAGAAGCUCAUUCGGAAGCCAAAACCAGUGGACUCCUGUGGGCUGGAUUGGCACUGCUGUCCAUUCAGGGUGGGGCACUGGCCUGGCUCACGUGGUGGGUGUACUCCUGGGAUAUCAUGGAGCCAGUUACAUACUUCAUCACAUUUGCAAAUUCUAUGGUCUUUUUUGCAUACUUUAUAGUCACUCGACAGGAUUAUACUUACUCAGCUGUUAAGAGUAGGCAAUUUCUUCAGUUCUUCCACAAGAAAUCAAAGCAACAGCACUUUGAUGUGCAGCAAUACAACAAGUUAAAAGAAGACCUUGCUAAGGCUAAAGAAUCCCUGAAACAGGCGCGUCAUUCUCUCUGUUUGCAAAUGCAAGUAGAAGAACUCAAUGAAAAGAAUUAAUCUUACAGUUUUAAAUGUCGUCAGAUUUUCCAUUAUGUAUUGAUUUUGCAACUUAGGAUGUUUUUGAGUCCCAUGGUUCAUUUUGAUUGUUUAAUCUUUGUUAUUAAAUUCUUGUAAAACAGAAGUAUUGUUUGAAGUUCUCAACUGAGAUUUUUACUUUUUGGAUUUUUAUGACUUGCUAAUGUUAGAAAGGGCUUGUAUGCGUCUAUCAAAGCAACGGUGGCUGCUGUUAGCUAAAAAUCCUUGUCAGCUUGUCCCACGUUUAUUCUCUAUGUGGAGGUGAAAGGGUCUGUGCUUGGCAUUCACUUCCAUUCUUAGACUUAAUUUGGAAUCAUCCUUUUAAAAAAAUCAGAGACCAGGUCUUGCCAAAUCAAACUCCUGGGCUCAAGCAACCCUCCUGCCUCAACCUCCCACGGAAUCGUCUUGUCAUUAACUUCUUUUUUUAAUAUGCAGUAGUUGGGAGUAAGAUCUUUUUAUCAUUUAUCAAAAAGGCAUAAAUGUUCCACCAACCAUAAAGUAUAGUUGGUACUUUUUGAACUUCAACUGAAACAGUGUAUAUAAACGAUUGCUUUUGAACCUGCAAAUCACAAGUUUCAGGUAUCGAAGCCAAAACAGUUAACUUUCUUCAGCCUCUGGCAGAUUAUUAACAAAACAGUAUUAUUCAGAUUCUAUAUCAUAUUAAUAAGAAUUGAACCUUGAAAGUAACAUCUGUUAUUCUAUUAAUGUGAUUGUGUGUGAAUGGGUCUGAUGACUGUUGGACUGUUUGUAGGAACUUAACAUGGAAGAUGCUGACAGAAUCAGAUUUUGCAGGUGUUCAACCUAUAGUGGCUAAGAAUUAUGUUUUCUAUUUCAUCCUCAGAAUGCCAUACAACAAUUCUGGAAUGCUGAUUUUUUUUAAAGUAGGAAUUAAAGUCAUACACAAAAUGUGGUAAUUCAUAUGUAGAUGAAAUAUUAAACAUUUAAAUGACCGAGUAAAAAACAUCUAUCAAUUACACAAAUGAACAAGAAUGUGAGUUAGAAAAAUGUAAUAAAAUAUGAAUUUCGAAUAUUUUAUUAAGGGAUGAUUUAAUUCCUGGAUUUCAAAAACCUUUAAAAACAUCAAACAAUAAACUUUUAUAAAAAAGUGA